AAAUGCGUGCUACGUCACUGUGCGAUCGGGUUGUGCUUAGCUUGGGGUCUCCUGGCCCCUUGACGCGUCAGGUUGCUGUACCCCUGCAUCGGAUGCGCUGUACCCUGCGCUGGCUCCGUGAACCUUAGGGACAACACCGGGACACCCGCGAGGCCGGAAAAUGGACUCAGUGGCUUUUGAGGAUGUGUCUGUGAGCUUCAGCCAGGAGGAGUGGGCUCUGCUGGCUCCUUCACAGAAGAAACUCUACAGAGAUGUGAUGCAGGAAACAUUCAAGAACCUGGCAUCUAUAGGGGAAAAAUGGGAAGACCCGAAUGUUGAAGAUCAACACAAAAACCAAGGACGAAAUCUAAGAAGCCAUACGGGAGAGAGACUCUGUGAAGGUAAAGAAGGUAGUCAAUGUGCAGAAAACUUCAGUCCCAAUCUCAGUGUGACGAAGAAGACUGCCGGAGUAAAACCAUAUGAGUGUACUAUCUGUGGAAAAGCCUUCAUGCGUCUCUCAUCCCUUACUAGACACAUGAGGUCUCACACUGGAUACGAGCUAUUUGAGAAGCCAUAUAAAUGUAAGGAGUGUGAGAAAGCCUUUAGUUAUCUCAAAUCCUUUCAAAGACAUGAAAGGAGUCACACUGGAGAAAAACCCUAUAAAUGUAAACAAUGUGGAAAAACCUUCAUAUAUCACCAGCCCUUUCAAAGACAUGAGCGGACUCACAUUGGAGAAAAACCCUAUGAAUGUAAGCAAUGUGGAAAAGCUCUUAGUUGUUCCAGUUCGCUUCGAGUUCAUGAAAGGAUUCACACUGGAGAAAAGCCCUAUGAAUGUAAACAAUGUGGGAAAGCCUUCAGUUGUUCCAGUUCUAUUCGAGUACACGAAAGAACUCACACUGGAGAGAAACCCUAUGCAUGUAAGGAAUGUGGGAAAGCCUUCAUUUCCCACACAAGUGUUCUAACACACAUGAUAACACACAACGGAGAUAGACCUUAUAAAUGCAAAGAAUGUGGAAAGGCAUUCAUUUUUCCCAGUUUUUUACGAGUACAUGAAAGAAUUCACACUGGAGAGAAACCCUAUAAAUGUAAACAAUGUGGUAAAGCCUUCAGAUGUUCCACCUCCAUUCAAAUUCAUGAAAGAAUUCAUACUGGAGAGAAGCCCUAUAAAUGUAAAGAAUGUGGGAAAUCUUUCAGUGCACGCCCAGCCUUUCGAGUACACGUGAGAGUGCAUACUGGAGAGAAACCCUAUAAGUGUAAAGAAUGUGGGAAAGCCUUUAGUAGAAUCAGUUACUUUCGAAUACAUGAAAGGACUCACACUGGAGAGAAACCCUACGAAUGUAAAAAAUGUGGGAAAACUUUCAAUUAUCCUCUAGAUUUGAAAAUCCACAAGAGAAAUCACACUGGAGAAAAACCCUAUGAGUGUAAGGAAUGUGCAAAAACCUUCAUUUCUCUUGAGAACUUUCGAAGACACAUGAUCACCCACACUGGAGACGGACCUUAUAAAUGUAGGGACUGUGGGAAGGUGUUCAUUUUUCCUAGUGCGUUACGAACACAUGAAAGAACUCACACUGGAGAGAAACCCUAUGAAUGUAAACAAUGUGGAAAAGCCUUUAGUUGUUCUAGUUACAUUCGGAUACAUAAAAGAACUCACACUGGGGAGAAACCUUAUGAAUGUAAGGAAUGCGGGAAGGCCUUUAUUUAUCCCACAAGCUUUCAAGGACACAUGAGAAUGCAUACUGGAGAGAAACCCUAUAAAUGUAAAGAAUGUGGGAAGGCCUUUAGUCUUCACAGUUCCUUUCAAAGACAUACAAGAAUUCACAAUUAUGAGAAACCUCUUGAAUGUAAGCAAUGUGGAAAAGCCUUCAGUGUGUCCACAUCCUUAAAAAAACAUAUGAGAAUGCACAAUCGAUAGAAACUCUAUAAAUGUGAGAAAUAGGAGAAAGUUUUCAAUUCUAACAGAUGCUUUCAAAGUUGUGAAAAUUCCCACUGAAGAGAGAAAUCCUGUCAAUGUAAGUAAUAUAGAAAGCGAGAUACAAGAUGAUUCAUGUAUAGUCAGGUACCACAUAAUCAUGUUUCAGUCAGCAAUGGACCAUAUAGGUUGGUAGCCCCAUAAGAUUAUAUAACACCUAAAACAUUUCUAUCAACCGCAAUUUAGUAGCAGUAGUAACACCAUAGUGCAGCACAUUAUUUAAGUGUUUAUGGUGCUGGUGUAAACGUGCUGCACUUUCAGUUGUAUAAAAGUACAAGACAGCGGCCGGGGACGGUGGCUCACGCCUGUAAUCCCAGCACUUUGGGAGGCCAAGGCGGGCGGAUCACGAGGCCAGGAGAUCAAGACCAUCCUGGCUAACACGGUAAAACCCCAUCUCUACUAAAAAUACAAACAAUUAGCCGGGCGUGGUGGUGGGCGCCUGUAGUCCCAGCUACUUGGGAGGCUGAGGCAGGAGAAUGGCAUAAACCCAGGAGGCCGAGCUGACAGUGAGCUGAGAUCCGGCCAACAGAGCGAGACUCUGUCUCAAAAAAAAAAAAAAAAAAAAAGUACAACACAGCUGGGCAUGGUCACACCUGUGAUCCCAACACUGGGAGACUAAGGCAGUAGGAUUGCUUGAUGCCAGGACUACUCUGGUCAACCUAGUGAGACCCUGUCUCUACAAAAAAUAAAAACAUUUUCUAAGUGUGGUAGCACACCCUGUAGUCCCAUCUACAUGGGAGGCUGAGGCAGGAGGAUUGCCUGAGCCCAGGAGUUCAAGGCUACAGUGAACCAAGAUCACGUGAUGGCAGUCCAGCAUGGGUGACAGUGAGACUGUAUCAAAAAAAAAAAAAAAAAAUUGGCUGGGCACAGUGGCUCAUACCUGUAAUCCCAGCACUUUGGGAGGCUGAGGUGGGAGAAUCAGUUGAGGUCAGGAGUUCAAGACCAGCCUGGUCAACAUGAUGAAACCCUGUCUCCAUUAGAAAUACGAAAAUUAGCUGGGCGUUCUGGUGUGCCUGUAGUCCCAGCUACUUGGGAGGCCAAAGCAGGAGAAUCGCUUGAACCCGGGAGGUGGAGAUUGCAGUGAGCUGAGAUCUACCACUACACUCCAGCCUGGGUGACAGAGCGAGACUCCGUCUCGAAAAAAAAAAAAUUACAGCACAGAUGUGCAAUAUAUACUUGAUAAUAAAUGGCUAAGUUACUGGUUUAUAUAUUUACAAUCCUGUUUUAGAAUGUAUUCCUGUGUUUUUUUAACAGUAAGACAGUCUCAGGCAGGUCCUUAAGGAGAUAUUCCCGGAAAAACUUUGUUAUGAUAGGCGAUGACGGCUCCAUGUGCAGGACUGCCCCUGAACGUAUUCUGGCGGGACAAAACAUGGAGGCAGAAGACAAUGAUAUUGAUGAUCCUCACCCCGUGUAGUCCUACACUAAUGUGUGUUUGUGUCUUAGUUAGUCUUUAACAAAAAUAGUUUAAAAAAAUUUAAUAGAAAAAGCUUAUAGAAUAUGGACAUAAAAUAUUUUUGUACAGCUGUACAAUGUGUUUUAAGCUAAAUUAUUACAAAGUUUUUAAAAAUAAGUUUAUAAAGAAAAUAAUGUACAGUAAGUUAAGGUUUAUUCAUUAUUGAGGAAAAAAUGUUUUUAUGAAUGUAGUGUAGUCCAAGUGUACAGUGUUUAUAAAUUCUCCAUUAGUGUACAGUAACAUCCUGGGCCUUCGCAUUCACUCACCACUCAACUGACUCACCCAGAGCAACUUCUAGUCCUGCAAGCUAUGUUCAUGGAGUGUCCUAUGCAGGUGCAUCCUUUUUUAUCUUUUAUACUGCAUGUUUACUCUGUGUAUUUUCUGUGUUUAGACUCAUAAAUACUUAACAUUUUGUUACAAUUUCCUACAGUGUUCAGUACAACAACAUGUUGUAUGGUUUAUAGCCUAGUAGCAAUAGACUGUACCAUAUAGUCUAGAUGUGUUGUAGCUAUACCAUCUAGAUUUGUGUAAGUUCACUUUGUGAUGUUUGUACCAUGAGGAAAUCACCUACAACACGUUUCUCAGAACAUAUACCCAUGAUUAAGCAAUCUCUGCCUGUAAAAUGCUCCAGAAAAUUCACACCAUGAUAUAAAUUCAUCACACACGAUAUAAAAGUUAAGGCAAGGCAUGGUGGCUCAUGCCUGUAAUCCCAGCACUUUGGGAGGCCAAGGCAGGCAGAUCACCUGAGGUCAGGAGUUCGAGACCAGCCUGGCCAAGACGGUGAAACCCCAUCUCUACUAAAAAUACAAAAAUUACCUGAGCGUGGUGGCAUGCACCUGUAAUUCCAGCUACUUGGGAGGCUGAAGCAGGAGAAUCAUUUGAACCUGGGAGGUGGAGGCUGCAGUGAGCUGAGAUUGUGCCACUACACUCCAGCCUGGGCAACAGAGCAAGACUCCAUCCCACACACCAAAAAAAAGUUAAAAAUUUUUUAUCACUGGCUCAUUCUUCAAGUACAUCUCUGGACUAUGAAUUGUAACUUAACUACUUUUCCAAGAAGUCUUGGAAGUGAGAUAAUUCUGUAAGUACUCUUUAAGCAGUGGUCAAAAGUUUAAAAGGUUGUGUUUUCUCAUUAAAUCAGUUAGUAAAACUUUUCUCUUUCUCUUGAUGUCUUGAUUCAUGAGUAAACUGAAGUGUAUUUUUUUUUUUUCGAGACGGAGUCUUGCUCUGUUGCCCAGGCUGGAGUUCAGCGGUGUGAUCUCGGCUCACUGCAAGCUCCGCCUCCCGGGUCCACGCCAUUCUCCUGCCUCAGCCUCCCCAGUAGCUGGGACUGCAGGCGCCCGCCACCAUGCCCAGCUAAUUUUUUUUGUAUUUUUAGUAGAGAUGGGGUUUCACCGUGUUAAGCCAGGAUGGUCUCAAUCUCCUGACCUCGUGAUUCGACCGCCUCAGCCUCCCAAAGUGCUGGGAUUACAAGCUUGAGCCACCGCACCCGGCCUGAAGUGUAUUUUUUUUUUCUUUUAAAGACCAGUGUUAGUAGAAGUGUAUUUUUAAUAUACAAUUAGUUUUAAUUUGUGUAUAGUUUUUCAGUUGUUCUCUGAAUAAAGAGAUUGUUGAAUACUGACACACUGUAACUAGGAUUUUUCCUACUGGCCUCAUGUGGAAGGUGGUGCAUAUAUUACCCAUUAUAUAUUUAUUUCACCUUUUCCGAAAAACUGCUUUUUAAAUUUCUUGGCCAGACACGGUGGCUCACUCCUUUGUAAUUCCAGCACUUUGGGAAACCAAGGCAAGCAGAUCACUUGAGGUCAGGAGUUCGAGACCAACCUGGCCAACAUGGUGAAAUCCCAUCUCUACUAAAAAUACAAAAAUUAGCUGGGCAUGUUGGAGGGCACCUGUAAUCUCAGCUACUUGGGAGGCUGAGGCAGGAGAAAUGCUUGAACCUGGAAGUCAGAGGUUGCAGUGAGCCAAGAUCACACCACUGCACUCCAGCCUGGACAACAGAACGAGACUCCAUAUCAAAAAAAUUAAAUUAAAAUAUAAUAAAUUUCUUGCCGGGCGCAGUGGCUCACACCUGUAAUCCCAGCACUUUGGGAGGCCGAGGUGGGCGGAUCACGAAGUCAGGAGAUUGAGACCAUCCUGGCUAAUACAGUGAAACCCCGUCUCUACUAUAAAUACAAAAAAUUAGCUGGGCAUGGUGGCGGGCGUCUGUAGUCCCAGCUACUCAGGAGUCUGAGGCAGGAGAAUGGUGUGAACCCGGGAGGCGGAGCUUGCAGUGAGCCGAGAUCGUGCCACUGCAAUCCAGCCUGGGCAGCAGAACGAGACUCCAUCUCAAAUAAAUAAAUAAAUAAAAUGAAUUUCAGCUAGAAGAGCCUUAUUCCAUUUUCCUUUUUAUUAAACAUCUGGCAUAAGUUGGUAAGUAUGUGAAGUUUAUCAUAUAUUCUUAUGCGAAUUAUUAUUUUCGCCUUUUUUUUAUAAUUCUGUCUGGGAUUUGAAUAGUAGAGUUUGAAUUCAGGAAGGACACCUGUGAUAGGACAAUAAAAUCUAGAGCUGGACGUGGCCCUCCUGCUACCUGUCGACACAGGUAAAUUUCCUAGAAUCUGUUCCCUUUAUAGAUCCAUGUUGAAAUUCACUUAUAGCCUCACUUGCAUGAGAUUUGCCAGGCAGAAGUGAAGAAGACAUUAGUCAGGUAUUGGAACCCCACCAUACAGGGAGACAGCCUGCUUCCUGCUCAUUUUCCUGGUUAUUUUCUCUGCCAAUCAAAAGUAUCCUGAAAACACCCUGAGCUGCUUGACUUCCAUUCUCAAAGAGAUGUGUUGGUUUCCACAGUUGUCUCCACAAGCUCCGCAUCAAAGAUCCACGUACAGUUUGGAUUUUCCUUCUAGCCUUCAUGUGUGGCCCAAGCAUCUAUUUCAGACUGUCAUGGUUGGCAUUGUUCUCUGAGGUUCUGUCUUCCCUUUGUGUUUCUAUGAGCUUUAAUUUGUAUGGUUCUUGUUCUGUUAAUGCCACUAGGGACUAUGUAUUCCUGAUUCCACCAUGACAGCUACAGUAAAACAGUAAAAAAAAAAAAAAA